GCUUGGCAGUUUCCCAUUGCGGGGCAGCUGGGCCGGGGGCGGGGGUCGGCUGCAGAUCUCCCGUUGUGUGAGAGAAACGCAAGCACGGAGCUCCCUUGACCUGCUGCAUCCUCCUCGGCAAUUUUUUUUUUUUAAGUCAAAAAGCUUGGAUUUCCUGAAAUUGUUGAACUGGAUGCGCGCGGAGUCUGGGGCGGAGGCGAGCGGCGGGUGUGCGCGACUCGGGGUGAUUCACGCCGGGGACCCCAAGGAGGUGUUGGCUACGUUUGUGGUUUUAAGAAAGCCUGAGGGCCUGAAGGCAGCCCCUGGAGAAGCCCUUUCCGAGGGCAUUCGGAACCUUCUGGUCCUAGAGGUGAAGCUGAACUGUCACCAGGACUUAUGACCCGCGGCUUCGCUCCCAUUCUGCCCGUCGAGUUCCACAAGAUGGGCUCCUUCCGCAGGCCUAGACCGCGCUUCAUGAGCUCCCCCGUGCUCAGCGACCUUCCCCGAUUCCAAGCAGCUCGGCAGGCUCUGCAGCUGAGCUCCAGCUCAGCCUGGAACAGCGUUCAGACUGCUGUGAUCAACGUUUUCAAAGGGGGUGGCUUGCAAAGCAACGAGCUCUAUGCCCUGAACGAAAACAUCAGGCGGCUGUUGAAGAGUGAACUUGGAUCAUUCAUUACAGACUAUUUUCAGAACCAGCUUCUUGCAAAAGGACUGUUCUUUGUGGAGGAGAAGAUCAAGCUGUGUGAAGGUGAAAAUCGCAUUGAGGUUCUGGCUGAAGUCUGGGACCACUUCUUCACUGAGACUCUCCCUACCCUGCAGGCAAUAUUUUAUCCAGUUCAGGGCCAGGAGCUGACUAUCCGCCAGAUCUCCCUGCUGGGCUUCCGAGACCUAGUCUUGCUGAAGGUGAAGCUGGGUGACCUGCUGCUGCUGGCCCAGUCCAAGCUGCCCUCGUCCAUUGUCCAGAUGUUGCUCAUCCUGCAGAGUGUUCACGAGCCCACAGGCCCAAGUGAGAGUUAUUUGCAACUGGAGGAGCUGGUGAAGCAAGUGGUUUCUCCUUUCCUCGGCAUCAGCGGGGACCGUAGCUUCUCAGGCCCCACGUACACGCUGGCCAGGCGGCACUCCAGGGUCCGGCCCAAGGUGACUGUCCUGAACUAUGCCUCCCCGAUAACCGCAGUCAGCCGGCCACUGAAUGAGAUGGUCUUGACCCCACUGACAGAGCAGGAGGGGGAAGCCUACCUGGAGAAGUGUGGCAGCGUGCGGCGGCACACGGUGGCCAAUGCCCACUCGGACAUCCAGCUGCUGGCCAUGGCCACCAUGAUGCACUCGGGCCUGGGGGAGGAGGCCAGCAGUGAGAACAAGUGCCUGCUCCUGCCACCCAGCUUCCCCCCGCCCCACCGGCAGUGCUCCAGUGAGCCCAACAUCACUGACAACCCUGACGGACUGGAGGAGGGGGCCAGGGGCAGCCAGGAGGGCUCGGAGCUGAACUGUGCUUCCCUCAGCUGAGUCGCCACCCCUGGGCCUUUCCAUCUCCUGUUUUGCAACCAGGAUGAGGACCCCUCCAUCUCCGUGGAUUACUGAGGGGGGCUCUUGCUUUAUGCGAUGCUGCCUUAUUUCCUUUAGGGUACUGUCCUGGUCAAAAUGACCUAAGGGGAAACCGUUGUUGUAAACCUCUUUAUUUUGGUGACUGUGACCACUUCUUUGUAGCCACCAAUUGUAGUGACCAGUUGCCUAAUGGUCACUUUCUGACUCCAGCCUUGCCAGCCUGACUCAGAUCCUCAUCUCUGGGCCUUUCUCCCUCCGAUGUUGGACUGCCUGAUGCUCCCAAUGACAUAUCCAAUGCUCCUGGCAUUUCUGGAGCAGGAGGUUGUCAGGACAACACAUAUAACCACCAAGGAUGUGUUGGCCUUUGGAGUUCCCCUUUAGGUUCCUAGUGAUGUGGAGGUUUAUGGGUGAAAAAUUAGUGGAGAGGGAACUCCUCUCCCCCAUUUUGUGUAGAGUGAAAAUAGCCUGAAGCCCCUACUCAGCAGGGCUCUGGGAAUGUGCCUUCCUUAUUUUAGUUUCAGAAUUGCUGGGAAAGUUACCCCACUGGUGGGUGAGGAUCUAUCCUCAACCUACAUCCAGAUCCUAUGUGCUGCUUGCACAGAGGCCUUUGGCUUUUGACCCAGGAGGGCCGCGAGGCUGGAGCUGCCCUGUCUUUCAUUGAGCCUUAGCAUUUCCCUCUCAGGCUUCCUCUCAAGCUCAAGGAACUCACCCCCAGAUAAGAAGCUGGUGCCUCUUGUCUCUCUCAUUUCAGAAACGGACUUUCUCAUCAUGCUUUCCUAUGGUGGGUAUGAGGGGCCAGCUGAUACCAACCAACUGGCCUGUAUCUAUCUAUCUGGAUUUGACUUGAAUUUUUAAAAUGUGUAUCGUUUAAAAAAAAAAAUGUUUGCAAAUUUUGCACAUAGGAUCUUGCACUGUUCAUUUUCAGUGGGGUGAGUCUUCACACUAAAAACACAAGCAGAGCUCCUGGGAAAAGAGACUGGAAGUGGUUCAGGAUAAAGAGAUCCAUGGUGGGCAGGGCUGUUAGGUCACAGAGCUCUAGAAGCAGCUGGACUUGAACCCACAAUGGCUUGUGUAAAUUCGUAAAUUUCAUGGUUUCUAGGAAAAGCUGCAUUGGGGUGGGGAGACCCAGUUUGCCUCAUAGGCAGAGGAUUCUCCAGGAAGCAUGGAAAAUGGAAUGUUUCCAUGCUUUACAGUGCUGGGAGAGAGGGGAGAUGUGGGCAGGACCUUUUGGAAGGAUGUUUAUUCUCUGUGGUUAAAGAAAUGCUGAGAAUUUCUAGCAUGUGAAGCACUUGGGGGCAGCAGGCCUUGGCACGGUGCUGCAUCCUUCUACUGCUCCCUCCAGGUCUGGGGGCUUUUAUCCACCUUGAAUCCCUAUCCUCCUCUUUGUAGUUGUCGGUCUCACUGAUAACAGCUCCAGAAAAAAAGACAAGGCUCCCCCUCUGACCCUUCCUGUUGGUAUUUAUGAAAUCUCAAAGAGAUGAGCCACCUUGGCUUCCAAUAUGGCAAGAGGGUGCUGGGAGAAGGUGAAGAUCAGUCUAAGCUGCCACGGUGAUGAGACCUUCUCAUUAUGUAACUCUUGAUGGCAUUUCCCUUCUGAGUGAAGAUUUGAAAUAUGAUUGAUUAGAAUUGUGCUCUUGAUGGCUGGGAAUUUAGAAAUUUUAUUUUAAGAGUUAUUUCAUUUUCAUCCUAAGAGUGAUGGGAGAGAAAUGUCCAAAAGAGAUCUGCUGAUCUGCUGAGAGUUUCAAACAAACAAAAAAAUAAUCUCUAUGUAUGUGUUGGAUAAAGUCUACAGACUGACUAACAUGCAUUAGCAAAUGGAGCAUCAGUAGGUAGCAACAUGAUAAUUUAUGUAACUGAUAGCUUCUGUCCUUAUUAGUACACUUAACAUUUGAGACUAGUAUUUAUUGAUCCAGGCAAAGUAAUUAAUUAAUCAUGCUUGGGCUUACUUUUUCAGUUUGUAAGGUUAAGCAUAUGUGCAUGCGUGCGUGUGUAUAUAAAUGCCUUUUCCAUAUCUUAAAUGUCCCUGAUGAGGAGAGCAGUCAUCAAUUAAAUAUAUAAGCUCUUAAAAUGAGAAUGGAAGUGUCAGUAUAGACCCAGUGUACUUAAGUGCUGAUGACUGUUAGCCAGUUUACAACUUUUUACCAUCGAUGUACACAUUUGAUAUUUGUGCAGUAAAUAGACUGUACCUAUAAAAAAUUUUAUUGAUGUUUAUGGUCAUGUUAGCUAUCAGAGAGCUAUUGGAGUGAGAGCUGAGGUGUCCUUAACCACUUUUUCUCUCCUAGAUUCAUUUUCAUUAUUUAUGCUAGGAUUUUCUUAUGGUUGACAUUUGAUGACAGGAAGCAAUCAUGACUCUUCAAGUGAGCUCACAGAAACCUUUCAUGUUGUCUGUUUCCAAAAUGGAUUCAAUAAACAACAUUUUGUCCAUGUUA